ACUCGUGUGCGCGCUCGUCCGCCCGCCAGUCCUCUCAACGCGCGCUUGGCCGCCCGACGACGCGGGAGCCGCACGCGCCGGACGAGGCUCGCUGCGCUCCCUGUUGCCCAGCGCGGGCCCGUUGAGGCGGAGCCCUCAGUUCCCGGCCAGGACACGGUCUGGGCCGCCGAAUCUCCGGCCGAAGAGCGGCGGCGGCAGCGGCGGUGAGGAGACCGGGCCGGGGAAAGGCAGACAUGGCGGGGCUGUGGGUAUCGGGGGAGGGUGGUCCCGUCGCCCCUGCGGCCACGUCGAAGGCUCGCUGGCGGGCGGCGCACCGGGGACAGGGGAGGGGCAGGGGAUGGAACCAGGUUGCAUGGGCUCCGGCUCGGCGCCAGAGCGGGGCUGCGGGCCGCGAGGGCGGCCCGCGAGGCUUUCCGCGGGACCCUCGGCGGGCGCCUGAGGAAAAAGACGCCGCCUCAGGGCUCCUGCCACGUUUCCCACAGCGCGUUACAUUCCGCCUCCGGGUGGGCGACAACCCCGCGGCUUCCCACCCUCUGUCCACCCCCUUCGCGUCGGUGUUUUUUCUGGAGCUCCGCUUGUUUGCUGGAGAGUCGCGCCUCCGGGAAGCCGGGUCCUCGAACCCAGGGCCGCCCGCCGGGGACAGCGGACCCGCGGGGCAGGCGCACCCUGGCGAGGAUGUUGUCGGGGAGGCUGGGCAUUGGGCGCCAGGGCCCUUCCCCUUGAACUUGGGGAAAACCGGGAUUGCAGAAGUUGGGCGCAGCUCAAGGCGGUUCUUUCAAGAGCGGGUGGAGAUGUUUGAUCCCUCCUCACCUACCUCUCUCAAAACCCCAGCGGGAGAGCCUAGCAGCAGGUUUCGAUGGCUUCAGAAAGUCCAACUCUUAGCCCCUUGGAAAAUUAUUUCCCCUCUUCAUGGCUUUGUGGCGCCGCUGAGGUCGGGCCGGGGCUCCUCACCCCACGGGCCAGUCUUCUCGCGCCCUCCACCUUGGGAACGUCUAUCAGGAGAAAAAUGUGUUCCUAGAAACGUUUGCGAUUAGCUUUUCGUUACAAGGGAGGGAAAAGUACAAAAGUUAUAAACUCCUGCGAGGCCGAGCUUGAUUCUGGAUUCCCUUUGGGUUUUAUCCACGCAGCCGUGAGCAGAGGAGCCUUGUGGAACAAAGUAGAACUUGAGGAGCAGCCGCCGCGGUGACGAGGUCCCAGGAUGACGUCACCGUGCGAUAUUUAAAAUGGGAGCCUUUUGCUCUGAGUGUGGGUGGAGGACGCCUACUUACUCAAGACGCCUGAGGUCUUCUUGGCCCUGCUUGCCUCUGGUGGUUCUUGCCCUGACUGUAACUCUCCCUCUUUCACCUUUUGGUACUCCUAGAAUACUGGUGGGAGUGGGCUUAUUUUUCAGCUGUUCGAGCUAUCAUUUCUUCAAACGGGGAAAACAAAAGUCCAAAUGAGUCAUCUUGUGUUACAACCAAAAGCAACCACUAAGUGGUUCUUUCCUUCUUUUCUAUUUUUUUAUAUGAAGCAGAGCAAACAGAAACAAAUCCAGAACUCAGAUAUGUGGCACAUAGUUGGCAAAUGUAAUGAAUGAGGAGAAAGAUCUAGUUAAAAGAUUCAGUACAUUUCUUUAGUGUGGUUCCUUGUUUGCUUUGCUGGAGUGGAGGCUAAUGUAGUUCCAUCAGCAAAACUUUCUUCCCAACCCGUAUAUUAAAUUGCCUUGGGUUUUCUUUUCCAUCGUAUCGUGGUGGAAUAUAAACGUAGCUUUACAAAGUGGAAAUGGCUUACAUUUUUCAGGAGGAGGCUGCACAGCAGUCGUGGUGGGCUGGGGUUAUGUAUACGUGUACACUCGUGUGUGGACCCAUGCCCGGUGCCUGCUAGCUGGCUGUAGAAGGUGAAUUUCUCAUUCUAGGGUUCUGGGAGGAAGAUUUGUGUGCCUUCCCCUCCAUCAGGCUAUCUGCGGCUGCCAGCACACCUCUCAGAUAACUGUGUAGAAUUUAUUUCACAGUGAGGUUCCUUGUUUGAAUUUGCACUUGGAAUAAAGGAGUCAUAUUCUGAAGAGAGACUGAAAGAGCAGUUUGAGAAAAGAAAGCUAACAAUCAGCUUUAUUUUUUUGGAAAUGUGGGAACACAAACUACUGCUAGGGAAAAAAAUGAAGAAUGAAAUUGCUGCCGUUGUCUUCUUUUUCACAAGGCUAGUUCGAAAACAUGAUAAGUUGAAAAAAGAGGCAGUUGAGAGGUUUGCUGAGAAAUUGACCCUAAUACUUCAAGAAAAAUAUAAAAAUCACUGGUAUCCAGAAAAACCAUCGAAAGGACAGGCCUACAGAUGUAUUCGUGUCAAUAAAUUUCAGAGAGUUGAUCCUGAUGUCCUGAAAGCCUGUGAAAACAGCUGCAUCUUGUAUAGUGACCUGGGCUUGCCAAAGGAGCUCACUCUCUGGGUGGACCCAUGUGAGGUGUGCUGUCGGUAUGGAGAGAAAAACAAUGCAUUCAUUGUUGCCAGCUUUGAAAAUAAAGAUGAGAACAAGGAUGAGAUCUCCAGGAAAGUUACCAGGGCCCUUGAUAAGGUUACCUCUGAUUAUCAUUCAGGAUCCUCUUCUUCAGAUGAAGAAACAAGUAAGGAAAUGGAAGUGAAACCCAGUUCGGUGACUGCAGCCGCAAGUCCUGUGUACCAGAUUUCAGAACUUAUAUUUCCACCUCUUCCAAUGUGGCACCCUUUGCCCAGAAAAAAGCCAGGAAUGUAUCGAGGGAAUGGCCAUCAGAAUCACUAUCCUCCUCCUGUUCCAUUUGGUUAUCCAAAUCAGGGAAGAAAAAAUAAACCAUAUCGCCCAAUUCCAGUGACAUGGGUACCUCCUCCUGGAAUGCAUUGUGACCGGAAUCACUGGAUUAAUCCUCACAUGUUAGCACCUCACUAACUUCGUUUUUGAUUGUGUUGGUGUCAUGUUGAGAAAAAGGUAGAAUAAACCUUACUACACAUUAAAAGUUAAAAGUUCUUACUAAUAGUAGUGAAGUUAGAUGGGCCAAACCAUCAAACUUAUUUUUAUAGAAGUUAUUGAGAAUAAUCUUUCUUAAAAAAUAUAUGCACUUUAGAUAUUGAUAUAGUUUGAGAAAUUUUAUUAAAGUUAGUCAAGUGCCUAAGUUUUUAAUAUUGGACUUGAGUAUUUAUAUAUUGUGCAUCAACUCUGUUGGAUACGAGAACACUGUAGAAGUGGACGAUUUGUUCUAGCACCUUUGAGAAUUUACUUUAUGGAGCGUAUGUAAGUUAUUUAUAUACAAGGAAAUCUAUUUUAUGUCGUUGUUUAAGAGAAUUGUGUGAAAUCAUGUAGUUGCAAAUAAAAAAUAGUUUGAGGCAUGA